CAUUCUGCCAGGCUUUUCAUUUCCCACUUCAACCUCUCAGCUCCCAACAGUCACUUGAACUAUAGACCCCUUGGCCUCCAUUGGGGGCUCUCCUUAAGAGACUGAGGGAUCCCUGAGGGAUCCCCAAAAGCAAUGAUUAGAGGCUGAAAACAGAAAAAAAACUUUGGAAACAGACUGGAUGUUUUGUACACUCAGCUCCUGAUUGGUGCCCUCUGCAUAUAUAUUGUCAGGAUGUGGAAUCCUGAAGUCAGCGCCUUGCCUUCUCUUAGGCUUUGAAGCAUUUUUGUCUGUGCUCCCUGAUCUUCAGGUCACCACCAUGAAGUUCUUAGCAGUCCUGGUACUCUUGGGAGUUUCCAUCUUUCUGGUCUCUGCCCAGAAUCCGACAACAGCUGCUCCAGCUGACACGUAUCCAGCUACUGGUCCUGCUGAUGAUGAAGCCCCUGAUGCUGAAACCACUGCUGCUGCAACCACUGCAACCACUGCUGCUCCUACCACUGCAACCACCGCUGCUUCUACCACUGCUCGUAAAGACAUUCCAGUUUUACCCAAAUGGGUUGGGGAUCUCCCGAAUGGUAGAGUGUGUCCCUGAGAUGGAAUCAGCUUGAGUCUUCUGCAAUUGGUCACAACUAUUCAUGCUUCCUGUGAUUUCAUCCAACUACUUACCUUGCCUACGAUAUCCCCUUUAUCUCUAAUCAGUUUAUUUUCUUUCAAAUAAAAAAUAACUAUGAGCAACA